GCGUUGCAGGUCACUGUAGCGGGACUUCUUUUGGUUUUCUUUCUCUUUGGGGCACCUCUGGACUCACUCCCCAGCAUGAAGGCGCUGAGCCCGGUGCGCGGCUGCUACGAGGCGGUGUGCUGCCUGUCGGAACGCAGUCUGGCCAUCGCCCGGGGCCGAGGGAAGGGCCCGGCAGCUGAGGAGCCGCUGAGCUUGCUGGACGACAUGAACCACUGCUACUCCCGCCUGCGGGAACUGGUACCCGGAGUCCCGAGAGGCACUCAGCUUAGCCAGGUGGAAAUCCUACAGCGCGUCAUCGACUACAUUCUCGACCUGCAGGUAGUCCUGGCCGAGCCAGCCCCUGGACCCCCUGAUGGCCCCCACCUUCCCAUCCAGACAGCCGAGCUCACUCCGGAACUUGUCAUCUCCAACGACAAAAGGAGCUUUUGCCACUGACUCGGCCGUGUCCUGACACCUCCAGAACGCAGGUGCUGGCGCCCGUUCUGCCUGGGACCCCGGGAACCUCUCCUGCCGGAAGCCGGACGGCAGGGAUGGGCCCCAACUUCGCCCUGCCCACUUGACUUCACCAAAUCCCUUCCUGGAGACUAAACCUGGUGCUCAGGAGCGAAGGACUGUGAACUUGUGGCCUGAAGAGCCAGAGCUAGCUCUGGCCACCAGCUGGGCGACGUCACCCUGCUCCCACCCCACCCCCAAGUUCUAAGGUCUCUUCAGAGCGUGGAGGUGUGGAAGGAGUGGCUGCUCUCCAAACUAUGCCAAGGCGGCGGCAGAGCUGGUCUUCUGGUCUCCUUGGAGAAAGGUUCUGUUGCCCUGAUUUAUGAACUCUAUAAUAGAGUAUAUAGGUUUUGUACCUUUUUUACAGGAAGGUGACUUUCUGUAACAAUGCGAUGUAUAUUAAACUUUUUAUAAAAGUUAACAUUUUGCAUAAUAAACGAUUUUUAAACACUUGUGUA